AGAGCUGGGUUACUACAAGUGUGAACCGGCAGCCUGUCUGUUGCCACAGAAGAACUUGGUCACCACACUGAGAAGCCGUGUUUUCUCACCUCCCUGUUACUGUUGUAGCUGUAUCUGGCUUCUCUAGCAUUUUAAAGGAAUUUCUGAUUGAGGCGCUAACAGCUAAUUCCACAGGAGUUGUAAGGCAGCCUGUGCAUAAACUGAGACAGAAGUUUCUCCUCAGAGACUCUCUUUUUAUUAUUAUUAUUAUUAUUAUUGGCAAAGACUUCUGGCUCUCCUCAGAGGAAUACCUUGUUGCUUAAGAUGAGUGGCUGUAGAAAGCGGUGUAAACGUGAAAUACUGAAAUUUGCCCAGUACCUUCUCAGACUAUUAACAGGUUCUCUUCAUACAGACAGCGUGGAAGAUGAACUGGAGAUGGCCACCGUCAGGCAUCGGCCUGAAGCCCUUGAGCUUCUGGAAGCCCAGAGCAAAUUUACCAAGAAAGAGCUUCAGAUCCUUUACAGAGGAUUUAAGAAUGAAUGCCCCAGUGGUGUUGUUAAUGAAGAAACCUUCAAAGAGAUUUACUCGCAGUUCUUUCCACAGGGAGACUCUACAACAUAUGCACAUUUUCUGUUCAAUGCAUUUGAUACAGACCACAAUGGAGCUGUGAGUUUCGAGGAUUUCAUCAAAGGUCUUUCCAUUUUGCUCCGGGGGACAGUACAAGAAAAACUCAAUUGGGCAUUUAAUCUGUAUGACAUAAAUAAAGAUGGCUACAUCACUAAAGAGGAAAUGCUUGAUAUAAUGAAAGCAAUAUACGAUAUGAUGGGUAAAUGUACAUAUCCUGUCCUCAAAGAAGAUGCUCCCAGACAACACGUUGAAACAUUUUUUCAGAAAAUGGACAAAAAUAAAGAUGGGGUUGUUACCAUAGAUGAGUUCAUUGAAAGCUGCCAAAAAGUAAGUAAUGAAAGUGUAAUAACUAUCAAUUCAGCUAUCAUAACAGCUAAACUGAGUAUUAGCAGCUAGCUACCAUGAACUGGGCGAAAUAUAGAGAUCAUAUGCCUAAGUUUACCACUUCUACAACAUGCAGCAUAAGCCUACCACUCUGAAAACAAGCACCAAUUACAUAAUCAACAUUUAGAGUGCCCACUGAGUCAGGCUAUGGAGGAAACCCUGGGGAUACAAAAGUUGUACAUGUACUGUGUUGAUUCCCAAAUUCCUUAGAGAGUAUUCAUGGAGGAUAAAACAUACAUGAGAUUUGAAUUGCUCUUUGCCAAAACUUAGCAUCACUCAUAUAUUAUCUAUCAUAUCUCCACAGCAUUAGAAUUCCUAGAUAGCCAAGUAUGGCAUCACAACAGGCCAAGCUUCUAUCUGAUUUCUAAGAGAAAAGUCAUUGUUUUAGUGUAUGUGGACAAGAAAUGGCUCUUUGACUGAACUCACUAAUGGUCUUCAGUCACAAAAAAUAAACAGUGGAAAAUUUUCUCUGAAGAGAACUCCAGGUAGUAGCCUGUUAUCAAAGAAACCAGUGUUAGCUUACUUAGAAUUAUUUGACUUGAUGUGUGGGCAGAACCACAGUUAAAAAUUGUUAAGGCCUGGUACAGUAGCUCACAACUGUAAUCCCAGCACUAUGGGAGGCUGAGGCGGGAAGAUAACUUAAGGCCAGGAUUUUGAGUCCAAUGUGGGCAACAUAGCAAGACCCUAUCUAUCUCUACAAAAAAAAAUUAAGUUAGCUGGGCACGGUGGCACGUGGCUGAAGUCUCAGCUACUUGGGAGGCUGAGGCAGGAAGAUCACUUGAUCCCUGUUGAGCCAUGAUUGUGCCACUGCACUCCAGAAUGAUGGGCAACAGAAAUAGACUCUGCCUCAAAACUAAAAAAAGAAAAAAAGAAUUUUUCAAAUAAUCCUGAAAACAAAGAAAUCCGUUGUUUCUUUAGUUUUUCUCUUUAUUUUUAAAUUGUUGUUCUUACUUUUCUGGAUGUCUGCUUGUCUCUCAACUUGGAUUUCCAUGCAGUGGUCUUUGAGAGAAUUAAUUUGGUGACAUUAAGCUGCUUGACGGUGAUGUUACUUGGUUUCUAGCAGUGGAAGCCAUUAUUGGUUCAGCCACCAUUUACCACUACCAUAAACAGCUCAGUAAGUGCUAUUCACAUGCAACUGACAAGUGCUCCAAUAAUGCCCAAAGUCUGUCCCCUAACUCAUUUCUAAAGAAUAUGCUAAACUGAACACAGCCACUGAGCAGUGGUUUCUGCUCCCCAAUUCUUUCUCUGUAAUUGAGAGACCAUUCAUUUUUAAAGGCUCCUUCAGGCCAUGCAGCUUUAGCCAUAACUAGCAGACAGAAAGAGAGAUGAUUACUGCAAACAUGUUACCUCUUAAUCCACCACCCUGCCUCCUAUGCGCCAGCCUCCAAUCUUCAUGAACUGCUGGCUCAUACACACAAAUUUUCCUUGUACCUGUAUAAAAGUCUGUGUGAUUUGGCCUGUGAUCUACAUAGAAUGCCAAAAUUCUCAUUUGCUUUGACACACCUCUGCACCUCUGUAGUUUCCAUUUUGGCAUUAUGAUUUGAGAAAUAUCCUCUAUUAAUACCAAGUAAAGAUUUAAAUAAAGUGGUUUAAUGCCUGGUCAAUAGACUCCACAAAAUAUAAAAUGGGUCCUUCAUAGUCAUCUAUGUGGAAAAUGGAUAGAAUAGAAUGGCAUUUACAUUUGCAAACACUUAAUAUUUGAGCUUUUGGCAUAGGUGGUUGAGGUGGUUGAUGGGAGGAGGCAAUACUCAGGGGCAAAAUAGUGUACUUUUCCUUGCAGAUAUGCUGAAUUUAAUCGCUCUGUGUUUCUCCCUUACAGGAUGAAAACAUAAUGCGCUCCAUGCAGCUCUUUGAAAAUGUGAUUUAACUUGUCAAAUAGAUCCUGAAUCCAACAGACAAAUGUGAACUAUUCUACCACCCUUAAAGUUGGAGCUACCACUUUUAGCAUAGAUUGCUCAGCUUGACACUGAAGCAUAUUAUGCAAACAAGCUUUGUUUUAAUAUAAAGCAAUCCCCAAAAGAUUUGAGCUUUCAGUUAUAAAUUUGCAUCCUUUUCAUAAUGCCACUGAGUUCAGGGGAUGGUCUAACUCAUUUCAUACUCUGUGAAUAUUCAAAAGUAAUAGAAUCUGGCAUAUAGUUUUAUUGGUUCCUUAGCCAUGGGAUUAUUGAGGCUUUCACAUAUCAGUGAUUUUAAAAUAUCAGUGUUUUUUGCUACUCAUUUGUAUGUAUUCAGUCCUAGGAUUUUGAAUGGUUUUCUAAUAUAGUGACAUCUGCAUUUAAUUUCCAGAAAUUAAAUUAAUUUUCAUGUUUGAAUGCUGUAAUUCCAUUUAAAUUCCAUUUAUAUACUUUAAGGAAACAAGAUUACAACAAUUAAAAAAACACAUAGUUCCAGUUUCUAUGGCCUUCCCACCUUCUGUUAGAAAUUAGUUUUAUCUGGCAUUUUUAAACAUUUAAAAAUUAUUAAACAUUUAAAAAUUAGUUUAUUAUCAGAUAUCAGCAUAUGCCUAAUAAAACUUAUUUUAAUAAGCAUUUAAUUUUCCAUAAUAUGUUACAGCCAAGGCCUAUAUAAUAAUUUUGGAUUUGUUCAAUCUUUCUUACAGGCUGUUUUCUAUUGUAUCAAUCAUUAGUAUCAAUCAUUAAGUGGAAGUUGAAGAAGGCAUCAAACAAAACAAGGAUGUUUACAGACAUAUGCAAAGGGUCAGGAUAUCUAUCCUCCAGUAUAUAGUAAUGCUUAAUAACAAGUAAUCCUAACAGCAUUAAAGGCCAAAUCUGUCCUCUUUCCCCUGACUUCCUUACAGCAUGUUUAUUUAUAUUACAAGCCAUUCAGGGACAAAGAAAGAAACCUUGACUACCCCACUGUCUACUAAGAACAAACAGCAAGCAAAAUUAGCAAGCAAAAUUCACUUUGAAAGCACCAGUGGUUCCAUUACAUUGACAACUACUACCAAGAUUUAGUAGAAAAUAAGUGCUCAACAACUAAUCCAGAUUACAGUAUGAUUUAGCUCAUCAUAAUUCAGAUUAUUUUUAAUCAUCUUAGCCAAAACUGUAAAGUUGCCACAUUACUAAAGCCACACACAUCGUCCCUGUUUUGUAGAAAUAUCACAAAGACCAAGAGGCUACAGAAGGAGGAAAUUUGCAACUGUCUUUGCAACAAUAAAUCAGGUAUCUAUUCUGGUGUAGAGAUAGGAUGUUGAAAGCUGCCCUGCUAUCACCAGUGUAGAAAUUAAGAGUAGUACAAUACAUGUACACUGAAAUUUGCCAUCACGUGUUUGUGUAAACUCAAUGUGCACAUUUUGUAUUUCAAAAAGAAAAAAUAAAAGCAAAAUAAAAUGUUUAUAACUCUA